CUCAGCCGCCGGAGACGCCGCCGCCGCCGCCGCCGCCGCCACACCUAGUGGAGCAGCCGGGGAAGGCGGCUCGUUGGGGGCUGGGGCGGAGAGCGCCGGGGGUGGGGGCGGAAGGGCGGCGGGCGGAAGGCAGGAGGCUGCCGGGGCGCGGGCUGCUGCGGGAGAAGGGGCUCCGAGGAGUCCGCCGCGGCUCGCUCUGUCGCCGGCGCGGGAUUGGGGCGCGAGGGCCAUGGGCGCGCUCUCCUAAGGCGGAGGUCGCGGGCGGGAGGGGAGGAGGCCCGAGAGAGGCUGCUGCGAAGGCCGCGGGCCCGUGACUGGGCGCGAGGCGGCCGGCGGCGGCGGCGGCACCAGCACCACCAUGUCGCGCUCAGUGCUGCAGCCCAGUCAGCAGAAGCUGGCGGAGAAGCUCACCAUCCUCAACGACCGGGGCGUCGGCAUGCUCACCCGCCUCUACAACAUCAAGAAGCAAGGACAAGUUUGGAAGGCAUGUGGAGACCCCAAGGCAAAACCAUCCUAUCUUAUCGACAAAAACCUGGAAUCUGCUGUGAAAUUCAUAGUCAGAAAAUUCCCUGCUGUAGAAACCCGCAACAACAAUCAACAGCUUGCACAACUACAGAAAGAAAAAUCAGAGAUUCUGAAAAAUCUGGCAUUAUAUUACUUCACAUUUGUAGAUGUUAUGGAAUUUAAGGACCAUGUUUGUGAAUUGCUGAAUACUAUUGACGUUUGCCAAGUCUUCUUUGAUAUUACUGUAAACUUUGAUUUAACAAAGAACUACUUAGAUUUAAUUAUAACCUAUACAACACUAAUGAUACUGCUGUCUCGAAUUGAAGAAAGGAAGGCAAUCAUUGGAUUAUACAACUAUGCCCAUGAAAUGACUCAUGGAGCAAGUGACAGAGAAUACCCACGCCUUGGCCAGAUGAUUGUGGAUUAUGAAAACCCUUUAAAGAAGAUGAUGGAAGAAUUUGUACCCCAUAGCAAGUCUCUUUCAGAUGCACUAAUUUCUCUUCAAAUGGUAUAUCCUCGAAGGAAUCUUUCAGCUGACCAGUGGAGAAAUGCCCAGUUAUUGAGCCUCAUCAGUGCACCUAGUACAAUGCUUAAUCCAGCACAGUCCGACACUAUGCCUUGUGAAUACCUCUCUUUGGAUGCAAUGGAAAAGUGGAUUAUCUUUGGCUUUAUUUUGUGCCAUGGGAUCCUAAAUACUGACGCUACAGCACUGAACCUUUGGAAACUAGCUCUUCAAAGUAGCUCUUGCCUCUCUCUCUUUCGGGAUGAAGUUUUCCACAUUCACAAAGCUGCAGAAGACUUAUUUGUAAACAUACGAGGCUAUAAUAAACGUAUUAAUGACAUAAGAGAAUGCAAGGAGGCAGCCGUGUCACAUGCUGGUUCAAUGCACAGAGAAAGACGCAAGUUUUUAAGAUCUGCACUGAAGGAAUUGGCUACUGUCCUCUCUGAUCAACCUGGAUUGCUAGGUCCCAAGGCACUUUUUGUUUUUAUGGCAUUAUCCUUUGCCCGUGAUGAAAUCAUCUGGCUACUUCGUCAUGCAGAUAACAUGCCAAAGAAGAGUGCAGACGACUUUAUAGAUAAGCACAUUGCUGAAUUAAUAUUUUACAUGGAAGAACUUAGAGCACAUGUGAGGAAAUACGGACCUGUAAUGCAGAGGUAUUACGUGCAGUACCUUUCUGGCUUUGAUGCUGUUGUCCUCAAUGAACUCGUGCAGAAUCUUUCUGUUUGCCCUGAAGAUGAAUCAAUCAUCAUGUCCUCUUUUGUUAACACUAUGACUUCCCUAAGUGUAAAACAAGUUGAAGAUGGGGAAGUAUUUGAUUUCAGAGGAAUGAGAUUAGAUUGGUUUAGGUUACAGGCAUAUACUAGUGUCUCAAAGGCUUCACUUGGCCUUGCAGAUCACAGAGAACUUGGAAAGAUGAUGAAUACAAUAAUUUUUCAUACAAAAAUGGUAGAUUCCUUGGUGGAAAUGUUGGUGGAAACAUCAGAUCUCUCCAUAUUUUGUUUUUAUAGUCGUGCUUUUGAGAAGAUGUUUCAACAGUGUUUGGAGUUACCCUCUCAAUCAAGAUACUCAAUUGCAUUUCCACUACUUUGCACUCAUUUUAUGAGUUGCACGCAUGAACUAUGUCCAGAAGAGCGACAUCAUAUUGGAGAUCGCAGUCUUUCCUUAUGUAAUAUGUUCCUAGAUGAAAUGGCCAAACAAGCUCGAAAUCUCAUCACUGAUAUUUGCACAGAACAGUGUACCCUUAGUGACCAGUUGCUACCCAAGCAUUGUGCCAAAACUAUCAGUCAAGCAGUGAAUAAGAAAUCAAAAAAGCAGACUGGUAAGAAAGGGGAACCUGAAAGGGAGAAACCAGGUGUUGAGAGCAUGAGGAAAAACAGGCUGGUUGUGACCAACCUUGAUAAAUUGCACACUGCACUUUCUGAGUUAUGCUUCUCUAUAAAUUAUGUACCAAACAUGGUGGUAUGGGAACAUACCUUUACCCCACGAGAAUAUUUGACUUCUCAUCUGGAAAUACGCUUUACCAAGUCAAUUGUUGGGAUGACUAUGUAUAAUCAAGCCACACAGGAAAUUGCAAAACCUUCAGAACUUCUAACAAGUGUAAGAGCAUACAUGACCGUACUCCAGUCAAUAGAAAACUAUGUGCAGAUUGAUAUUACAAGAGUAUUUAAUAAUGUGCUUCUUCAACAAACACAACAUUUAGACAGUCAUGGAGAGCCAACCAUUACAAGUCUAUACACAAAUUGGUAUUUGGAAACUUUGUUACGACAAGUCAGCAAUGGCCAUAUAGCAUAUUUUCCUGCAAUGAAAGCGUUUGUGAACUUACCUACAGAAAAUGAAUUAACAUUCAAUGCAGAGGAAUAUUCUGACAUAUCAGAAAUGAGGUCAUUAUCAGAACUACUAGGCCCAUAUGGUAUGAAGUUUCUAAGUGAAAGCCUUAUGUGGCAUAUUUCAUCACAAGUUGCUGAACUUAAGAAACUUGUGGUGGAGAAUGUUGAUGUGUUAACACAAAUGAGGACCAGCUUUGACAAACCAGACCAGAUGGCUGCACUGUUUAAAAGAUUAUCAUCUGUUGACAGUGUCUUGAAGAGGAUGACAAUAAUUGGUGUAAUUUUAUCCUUCCGAUCAUUGGCACAAGAAGCACUUAGAGAUGUCUUAUCCUACCACAUUCCUUUUCUUGUAAGUUCAAUUGAAGAUUUUAAGGAUCACAUUCCAAGGGAAACUGAUAUGAAGGUUGCAAUGAAUGUGUAUGAGUUAUCAUCAGCUGCCGGAUUACCUUGUGAGAUUGAUCCUGCAUUGGUCGUAGCUCUUUCUUCACAAAAAUCGGAAAACAUUAGUCCAGAAGAAGAGUAUAAAAUUGCCUGCCUUCUCAUGGUGUUUGUGGCAGUUUCUUUGCCAACACUGGCCAGUAAUGUGAUGUCUCAGUACAGCCCUGCUAUAGAAGGGCAUUGCAACAACAUACAUUGCUUGGCCAAAGCCAUCAACCAGAUUGCUGCAGCUUUGUUUACAAUUCACAAAGGAAGCAUUGAAGACCGUCUUAAAGAAUUUCUGGCGCUUGCAUCCUCCAGUCUACUGAAAAUUGGCCAGGAGACAGAUAAAACUACAACAAGAAAUAGAGAAUCUGUUUAUUUACUGCUAGAUAUGAUUGUACAAGAAUCUCCAUUCCUUACAAUGGAUCUUUUGGAAUCUUGUUUUCCUUAUGUCUUGCUGAGAAAUGCAUACCAUGCUGUCUACAAACAAAGUGUUACAUCUUCUGCAUAAAAUUACCUACUUAAUCAAGAUAAGCACGCAUUUUUGUUGCCUUGGUUUUACCUGUAGACUGUGGAACUAUUUUACCUUAAGACCUGAAAAAGUUUUGUGGAUUAUAAAUUUCUUUCAUACGGUUGUAUUUUCUGAUCAUUGGUUUCUUAAUAUGGUUGUACUACAGUAUACUUGGUUGAUUUAGGUUGCACAUUCACUGAAUUCACUGAGAUUAUUCCUAUAAUUUUAAAGUAUCAUUUAUUUGAAAAACAUACAUUAUCAACAUGUUUUUGAUAUUUGAUAAUGAAAAAAAUCUUUGCUUGUUUAUUUCUGAAAAAGAACUGUAUUUAGUGAUUAUUUUAGAUAGUGAUAUUAUAGUAUUCAUCUGUGUGUAAAUUAUUUCAUAUAGGGAAGAGUUCUGAUCUGUACCUAUGGUUCUUAUUGAAAACAACAUUGGAUGUGCAUUUCUGUGAUGUUAUGAAUACAUUUCUACUUUAUUUUGAAACAUUUGCCAAACUAAAUACUGUAACACUGUAUAACAUUUAAAAAUGUUAAAGAACUGCUUAGUAUUAGAAGCAGAUCAUUUCCCAAAAUUCUAAGAGCAGCAGCAUAUGUUGUUGCUUGUAUAAAGCCUAGCGAUAAUUUUUAGACUAACUUCCAUGGUGCCCUGUUGGCAUUAGCACUACCAUUGUACCCUGCUGUAUAAUAAACAAUCUUAGACAUUUAUCAACUGUUGAUACAAAUGUUAGUCCCUAACCACUUUUUAUAUAUGUUUUAAAUUUUUGAAAUUCAAGUGUACCUGCCAUAACAUAAAAUAAACACUAGACUGUAUCACACUUCGAUUGAUUUCUUUAAGAUCCUUGGAUAUUCGUUCAAUAAUAAUAAAGUUUUUGUUUAAACUUAGUUUGAAAUAUAAAAAAUAAUGGUUUAGGAAUGUCUAAGUACAGCAUUCGAUACCAGGUCAGCUAUUAUAUGAUUUGUUUAAAUGUUUUAAAAAACAUUUUAUUGAAAAAAAUACCAAAAUUAGAAAAUAAAAUUACACAAUACUUCUUAAAAAUUAAGAACUUAAAGAAAACUUGUAUGCUGUCAACUUGCUCAUUUUAUCUGUAACCAAAUAGAGUUAUUUAAAAGAAUAGGGAAAAAAAAUUGAGUGAUCAUGGGACUAGUGAGAAUGUUGAGAACUGCUGCAUUAGUCAGUAAUGAAUGGGAAAGACAUAAAAGGGCCUAUUGCUUAAUAGUUGGCAUGGAGGGCAAAGCAGCUCAUUUAGUUUGAAAACUAACCCAAUGUUUUGCUCUUUGAUUGGCAUUGUUGAGGCUGUUUCUCAGCAGCUUUGUAUAUGAAUAUCAUAAAGAGCUUCUGUUCACAGCUUCUUAUGUAUACACUGGUAACUUGUGUUAAGAUAAAAGAAGGCUGCUGUGAACUCAGUUAUAAUGUUUUUCUUUCUUCAAACAUAGAGAGUAGAAUGAAAUUGAAGUACUAUGAGAUUAUGCUAUUAUUUUGUGUAUGAUUUGUCCAGCCUAUAUUUAAAGUAGGGAGUAGUUGUCACUAUCUGUCGAAAAAUUGUACUUGUUCCAUAAAGAUUUUUUAAAAAGGGAAAUUUUAAAAUGGCAUAGUUCAGACCUGAAAUAGUCUGAUUUACACAGUGAGCAGUCAAAACUAAGAUUUAAUGCCGUUUGUUUUGAAAUAUUAGGAUCUUAGAGAGGUAAUAACUUUGUUGGCAGUGAUCUCUGGAGAGGUAAAGUAGGAAUUUGGAUAUGUACACUUUGGAAUCAUAUGUGAAAGGGCAUAAGGAUGAAAAUAAGGCAUUCUCUACCACUGCUAGGCUGAGAAAAAAAUCGCUCCUCAUAGUCACCUGAAGUUUUUGUCCAAAUUUUUUCUCAUACAGCAAAGGCGGGGGAGGAGGCGUGGCAAAGGUAACUUGGAGGAAAAAGUUAAAAGUAAAUUGACAACUACUAUUUUUAAUAUCUUGUUUGUUUUAUUUUCUUCUAAACUUACACAACAACAUACUAUUUUUGUUGUUUUCUCUACAUUAAUGUGAUCAUACCAUACAUACUGGCCUGUAAUCUGCUUAUUUCACUCAGUAGUAGAAAAAAUGUCUUUAAUAUUCUUUUUAAUACCUUUAUAGAUACCAUAACUAAUUUAACAAUUUCAUGGCCAGGCGUAGUGGCACACGCCUAUUUCAGCACUUUGGGAGGCCAAGGCGGAUGGAUCACUUGAGGUCAGGAGUUCAACACCAGCCUGGCCAACAUGGCAAAACCCUGACACUACUAAAAAUACAAAAAUUACCCAGGUAUGAUGGUGCACACCUAUCAUCCUGGCUACAUGGGAGGCUGAGGUGGAAGAAUUGUUUGAACCCGGAAGGAGGAGGUUGCUGUGAGCUGAGAUCACACCACUGCACUCCAGCCUGGAUGACAGAAUGAGACUGUCUCAAAAAAAAAAAGAAAAUACUCAUUUGGAUAGAUUGGAUAGAUUUUUAGACAAUUUCUUUUCAUUAUUAUAAAUGUAUAUCUAUAUCUUGGUAAAGUUGACCUGUUAUUUUUUUAGAAUAAUUUUUCAGAAGUAAAAUUGCUUCCUUUCUGCUGCUUUUUCAUUCACUUAUUUAAGCAAGUAUUUUUAGAUGCCUGCAUGUAAUGGUGAGCAAAAAGGUGACCCUUUUAUAGUUGAGCUUGGAUUUUAGUGAUGGUAUACAAUAAACAAACCAGCUUCUUGAGACGGAGUUUCACUCUUGUUGCCCAGGAAAUGGGCAAUGGCCUGAUCUCGGCUCACUGUAACCUCCGCCUCCCGGGUUCAAGCAAUUCUCCCAUCUCAGCCUCCUGAGUAGCUGAGAUUACAGGCGCCCGCCACUACGCCCAGUUAAUUUUUGGUAUUUUUAGUAGAGAUGGGGUUUUACCAUGUUGGCCAGGCUGGUCUCGAACUCCUGACCUCAGGUGAUCCACCCACCUCAGCCUCCCAAAGUGCUGGGAUUACAGGCAUGAGCCACCACGCCCAGCCAUGAGCAAACUUCUGAUGGUGACUGGAAAGUAUACAGGAUAAUGUGGGGAGGCAGUGGUGAAACUACUUUAGAAGAAAGUGUUAGAAGAAAGUGUCAUCUGUGUAAGAGAAAACAUUUGAGCUGGUACGUGAAGGAUUAGAAGGAACCACAAGUGGGCUGAGGGGAGGAAUAAUAAAGGCAAAGACCCAGAAGGCAAGCACAAACUUGGCAUGUUUGAGAAGUUAGAAGUGUGUCAUCUGUGUCUCUGUCAUGAGGAGUGCUCAAGUUCCCUCUAGGAGCCUUAUGGGCUAUCUAGCUCUUUUUCUCUUCUGAUCAUGUGCUUGCUUGCUUUCUUCUUUGCUUAUAUAGCAGAGUUCACAAAUUAAAUCUAAUGUAGGCUGGUUAAUAAAGGAAAUGAACAUGAAUUCACUGAUAGGCUCUUGCAUUAAUGUGAAAAUGUAAAGUCUGUUGUACACCAUCAGGCCUUCUAAAUGAAGCCCAAAUUCUGUAAGGUAGUGAAUUGUAACCUACUGAUUAGUACAUGAUCCAUGCCCAUUCUGUUAUAAGGACUUGCCUUUCUGAGACUUCACCUGUAUUAUUCCUAAGACUUUUGUGAAUAAUCCUUAAAGUAGUGACUCCUUACAUCUUUCUUUCAUUUCUUCUUUGUAGUCACUUGAAAUGACAGCAUGAACCAUCAUUUCAUUUGAAGGCCUGAGCCUGAAUUUUCAAAUAGACAAAAUGCUCUCUUUCUCCGAAGAUUUGCCAUGACCUCUGCCUUUGGGAAAAAAUAUUUGAGAUUUUAAAAUUUUUAUUCUGUAGUACAAAAAUUAUGUUUUUCGUUAAUUGGUCCUGUGGAAUUGGAAGGAAAUUUAAUAUUUAUUGACUCUACUUUGGUAUUAUUUUCAGAGUGAGAAGUAACUUUAAGUGUAUUAAAAUUUCAUUCAUUUUUGCAUGAACCAAACUUUCCCUACACAUCGCUGUCCUUGACUGUCCAGAGUAAACAUGUCUAACUCUGGAAUGUUUCAUUUCCAAUAAAAGUAUUCAGCCUGUCAUUUUGGGCCUAAGUAAAAUGGGAUAAAUUAGCAAUCUGAAGUUAGGAUCCUAGCCACAGAGGGCCAUGUCUCAUUUCUGGUUUAAGUGCACCCCUCAUCCCCAGCCCUUACCUUCUUCUUUCUCUUAAGGAUUGAGACAAUCCUCUUGGUGCUCUUGGUGCAGGUGCAUCUUGGUCACCUCUUACAUGAGGGCCACAAACUUGGUAAAUGGGUGGCCUGGAGAUGGGGUUGUACUAGGUAUGUGACCUUGGUGAUUGCCUUGUCUCAGUUGUAGUAUAUGGCUGAGUCACAUUCAUAGUACACUACAUACACAUACUGACCAAAUGCCAAUGGCUAAGGCUUGAAAUUAUUUCACCAAGACCUAAACUGAAGAUUACCAUCAUAAAAUAAGCUUCUAGAAUCCAUGAAUAAGUAGGAAAUCAUAUUUAAAAUUUACUGUAAUUUUAUUAAAGCUCAUUUUUUAAAUUUAAUGCAGUGCAGAGUCAUUAAUUUCUCAGCAGUAUCAGGUGCUAAAUUGCUCACUCAUUAAACUACUAAUUUAAGAUAGUUAUUUUAAAUUAUAGAACAGGAAGCAACUUACGAGGUUGCAACCAAAUUAUAUUUAUUUUUUCUCCAUUAGUAACUGACUAAAAGUGUUUUCUUCAACUCUGGGAUUUGAAGAUUUUGUGGUCAGUGGUGAUAUAAUUUCACUGAAGCGUGCUCACAGACUAAAACUGUGCACUACUCAGUGAUGCGUCCUGAAUGUUUUCAGAGACAAACCUAAGAUAAUGUUGCCCUUGUUUACUUUCAUUAUUUCUGAUUUUUUUUUUAUGCAUGUGUUUGCUGCAUCACACAAUUACUUAAGAAGUUGUCCCUAACCUUUGUGCUGUGGUCUGAAUGUUUGUGUCCCCCUGGCCACAAAAUUCAUAUGUUGAAAUCUGAUCAUCAGUGUGACAGGAUGUGGGGCCUUUGGGAGGUGAUUAGGUCAUGAGAGUGGAGCCUUCAUGAAUGGGAUUAAUGCCCUCGUAAAAGGGGCCCCAGACAGCCGACUUGCCCCAACCACCACGUGAGGACAAAGCAAGAAGCCACUGUUCAUGAACCAGAAAGCAGACCCUCCACAAACACCAAAUAUGCCAGCACACUGAUUGGCUUCCCAGCCUCCAGAACUAUAAGCAAGAAGUUUUUUUAUAGUAACAAAUUUAUUGUUCACAGUUCUUGCUUAUAAACUUUAUAAACCAGACUAAGGCAUUUCGUUAUAGCAGCCCACACGGACUCAUAUUUUGGUUCUAGAAAUGUGACACUGGAAUGAUGUGGCUCUCAAGAUGACAGUGUUGCUUCUGAAUGUCUAUGUUCAUGUCAUCUUUAAUUGCAUGAACACCAGUUUUAGCAUCUUCCCUUGAGUAGAAAGAGAUUCUCUACAGCAAGUAUUACGUAAGAAGUACUGGUGGCCAGGCACAGUGGUUCACGCCUGUAAUCCCAACACUUUGAGAGGCGGAGCCAGAGGUAUCAUUUGAGCCUAGAAGUUCGAGAGCAGCCUGGGCAAUAUGUCUAAACCCCAUCUCUACAAAAAAAAUACAAAAAUGAAAAAGCCGGGUGUGAUUGUGUACACCUGUAGUCCCAGCAACUUGAGAAGCUGAGGUGGCAGGAUUGCUUGAGCCCAAGGGGAGGGUUGGCGGCAGUGGGUGGUUCGAGGCUGCAGUGAGCCAUGAUUAUACCAGUGCGCUCCAGCCUAGGUGACAGAGCAAGAGCCGGUCUCGAUAAUAAUUAAGGCCAGACGCGGUGGCUCACUCCUGUGAUCCCAGCACUUUGGGAGGCCAAGGUGGAUGGAUCACCUGAGGUCAAGAGAUUGAGACCAACCUGGCCAACAUGGUGAAACCCUGUCUCUACUAAAAAUACAAAAAUUAGCUGGGCUUUGUGGCUCGCGCCUGUAAUCCCAGCUACUCAGGAGGCUGAGGCGGGAGAAUCGCUUGAACCCAGGAGGCGGAGAUUGCAGUGAGCCGAGAUCAUGCCACUGCACUCCAGCCUGGGCAACAGAACAAGACUCUGUCUCAAAAAAAAAAAAAAUUAUAAUACAUUAAAAAAAAAAAGCACUUGCAUUCUGAAGGCAUAUUCACCCUUGAACUGAUAGCAUUCAAUGUAUAAAACACAUGAGUUUCACUCCAAGUUACAUAUAGAAUGUUUAUCUUUAUUUGAGAGGAAAUAUCCAGUUAAUAAUCAGAAUGUCAUACUAAUUAGGUAUGACCAUAACUUACGUUAGUCACAUGGUCAUUGAUUGCAUGCAGAUUCUGGCUGCCAGAAAGCACAUUGAAGUAGGUAGUCAUUUAACCAUUUAACUGUUAGAUCUUGCAAAGGUUGAAGCUGAAGCUGAGGAGCAGGUAGUACACAACUUUACAGGUUAAUGCUGAAUGUCAGUUCAUUCUGAAUUCUUACCUUCAGCCAAAAGGUACAAGGGUCUUUGCAGUCUGAAGCAAGGCCCAGAUGGCAGAACUUGUGAUGGCUAGGAGGGGAAAAUUUGACCUUAACUGGUAGUUGUGGUUUUAUCAAGCCAAAAAUGCUGACUAGAAUAAUAAUGAGAGCUAAUGUUUAUUGAAAGCCCAUUGUGUACCAGAUACUCUGUUUUCUCUAAUUCAAACCUCUAAAUAUUGCUCUUUUAGUCUUCACAGUAAUCCUAUAUCAUGAUGACCCCCAUUUAUUGAUAUGGAAACUGAAGCUCAGGAAAGACAAAGCAAUUUUUACAAACUCACACUACAAGGAAGUAGCAGAGGCCAACAUUUAAAUCUGGCCCCAGAGUUGUGUUCUUCUCAUUAAACUGUGUCUCAGAUCUCUCAAAUGUGAGUGUGGACUUUUCUAACCAAUAGCAUUUUUUAAUUAAUGUUUUAAAAAUUUGAAUAGCUUUUAGGGUACAGUGGGUUUUUGUUUACAUGGAUGAAUCAUACAUUGGUGAAGUCUGAGGUUUUAGUGUACCUGUCACCCAGGUAGUAUGCAUUGUACCCAAUGUGUAGUUUUUUAUCCCUAGACCCGUUCCCAUCCUCCCACUUCUGAGUCUCCAAAGUCCAUGAUAUCACUCUGUAUGCCUUUGCAUACACAUAGCUUAGCUCCCACUUACAAGUGAGAACAUACGGUAUUUGGUUUUCUGUUCCUGAGUUACUUUGCUUAGAAUAAUGGCCUCUGGCUCCAUCAUAGUUGCUGCAAAAAGACAUUGUUUCUUUUUUUAUGGCUGAACAGUAUUCCGUGGUGUGUAUAUAUACCACACUUUCUUUGUCCACUCAUUGGUCAGUGGGCACUUAGGUUGGUUCCAUAUCUUUGCAGUUAUGAAUUGUGCUGCAAUAAAUAUACACAUGCAGAUUUUUUUUGAUAUAUUGACUUCCUUUGGGUAGAUACCCAGUAGUAGGAUUGCUGGAUCAAAUUCUAUCCAGUAGCAUUUGAAACUGCUUUACAUUAACAAUGAGGGACAAAAAAAAUAACAAUGAGGGCUUACAUUAUGCUACUCUUGAUACUAGACAUUUUCAUAUCCAUUACUUCAUUUAAACUCCACAACCAAAUUACUCAAUAGGGAUUGUUUUCUUUAUUUUUGUAAAUGAAUGUGGAAACCAGCUCAUAAAACUUUAAAUUCCUUGCCCCAGUGUCAUAAAAUUACUGAGUUUGAGUGGCAGUGCUGAGAUUAAAACCUAAGGCUCUAGGAUUUCCAGCCCAUAUUUUUUCUACUGUAUCAUGUUCUUUCCCAAAGCACUAAAAAACAUUUCCUGGGUAAAUGACUGUGGGCUUGGGGACACUAUGCCCACUUUCUGGCCUUCAUGGGUCUAAGUUGCUUCUUUGCUUCUUCACUUUUUCUCUCUGAUCCUGCUCAGAUUAAUCUCUAGUAAAUCAGAUUUCUUUCCUAGGCUGUCUUAUCCCACAUAUAUAGUAGAUAAUAUGUCACAUAUUUGUGAAUGUUAAAAAUAUUUGUUUUAGUUUUAAAUCUCAAGCUCACACAGUACUUACUCUCUAUGUUAACAAAAAUGGUUUUUACUAUUUUCUGAAGGUAACGCAGCUGUUGAAGUGAGAUCCUACACUGGAACAUACAACACUUGGUCUAAUAUUAAAGUUCGUGCCAAGAGCUCUCUAAAUGUGAUUGAUGGAUUAAUUCUGCCUUUAUGAAAGAUGAACUUAUUUUCAAGAUAAUAGCUAAUUCUUGAAUGGGCAACCUAUUAUGUAUCAAUGAUUGUAAUGAUGGAGCAUUUUAGUCAUUUGUAGCUGGAAGAGCCUUAGAGAUUAUCUGGUUCAACCUAUUCAAGAGUUAGGUAAUUUAACCAAAUUAACAUAUGUGGCGAUGUGCUCAUAUAGUGUUCCUUCCACUGUGCUGUGUUGCCGCAUAUAUGCUGAUCUUAUGUUUAUGCAGUAAUAGUCUUCAUAAUGAUAAACAGCUACUGGUUCCUGGUAGGAUUUUGGACGUGGAUAUGACUUGAAGUAUGAUGCCACAGCCUCAAACAAAUCUGGGGUUUGAAUCCCAGCUCUGUCACUUAUGGACAAAUUACUUAACUUCUCCAAGUUUGUUUCCCUAAGUGUAGAAUGUGGAUAAUAUCUACUUUAAAGGGCUAUUGUAAGCAUUAAAAUAAGAUCAUGCGUAUAAAUUGAUGAGAUGGUGGGGAAGAAGAGGCUACCACAAAGUAGGCAUUCAGUGUAAAUGGUGGUAGUUUCUCCAGUAUUAUUAGGCUAUUUGGUUUCACUUAUAAAAUUGCCUUCAAAGAGUUUUUUCAUGGCUUUUAUGAGUAUUAUAAUAUCAGAACUUCCACUCAUGCAAAUGUAACAUUUGUGUGUUAGUCUAUUCUAUAGCUCUGAUCGGAGUCUUUAUCUUAAAUGGGAAAGAUUAUUUUCCCUGUCAUGUAACUUUAACAGAAAACGAUGCUAAAAUUAAUUUUAAGACUGCUCUAUACUAUAUGUAUGUUAUACUAUAUUUUUAUAUACUAUACACAAAAAUGUAUAAGAUGUAAAGCUUGUAUUUUCAAAUGUUAUUGCAGUAUCCAGAACAAUUGCGACAAUUGCUCUUGGAAGCUUCUGUGCUUUUCCACAUGCUGUUCCCUGUCUCUGGAAUGGAAUGUUCUCUUAUUCUGGCUGGCAAACUCCUGAACAUAAUGUAAACAGUAAGCUCAAACAUCACUUGCCCUUUCCUUACCAUGCCAUCCUGUUUCUUCUAAACCUUAUAAAUGCCUUUAUUAUAGUACAUAUUGAAUCAUAAUGUAAUUAUUAUUUAUCUCUGACUCCUUUGAUUCUGGGACUGCCUUGAGGUCACGGUCUAGGUUUAUUUCAUCUUUCUGUCUGUUUAGUCAAAUUUCCUACCCUGUGUAACUCUCAGAAUCUUACUUUAAGUUAGGAAAGGCCAGUGGCUGGACAGAUGCUACAGACCUCCAUUGGUACAGAUGCCCUUAGCUUCAUGUUGGGAACAAGUGGUUCUGUUUCUUUUUGUUCCUGUGGAGAAGCAUCAGAGAUACAGGCAGCUGGGGAUUUCUACACCUGUAAUAGCAGCAGCUCAGUGAUGACACAGAGACAUGUUUUUUUUUUUUUUUUUUUUUUGACAGAAGGCGAAGGGGAAGCAAGGUACUUCUUACAUGGCAGAGGGAAAAGGAGAGUUGGAGUGGGGGAGGGGGAGAGGGAGGAGCAGGAGCAGGGAGACGGGGAGGGAGAGGAAACUGCCCCGAAGACAUGGUUUCUAAGAUUUCUCCCAAUGAGACAAAUCACUUGUCUGGGAUGUCAGGGGGAGAAGAUGCAGAAUCUGAGCCCCUUGUAUAAAUAGACAAAAGGUGAAAGCAUUGGCAAUAGAUCAAAAAGGCAUUCCACGUAGCAAAAAAAUUAUUUUUAAAUCUGAAAAUUUAAGUGAAAUGCCAAGAGCAAAGAAGAGAGGCCAUCAGAAAAAUUUCAAAGUGACUACUCAGGUCAUUGUCCUGAAAUAAAUGAUCAUUUUAUUCUGGUGACUCACCCCUAGCUAGAGUCAGUACUUCAUAGAAAAGACAGGAGCUGUGAGACACUUAACUGUAAUCUUACCCCUUUACAGAAAUGCCUCCUAUAGUCAAGCUGGUCUGAUGAUCUCAUGUCAUCAUGCACAAGGAUUAGCAAGCCUUGAAAUUUUAUCCUGUCAGUGUAACUCCUCAUCUAGUCUCAAGAUUGCACUGGCAGUUCUUUCGCAGCUGAUCGUACAGGGAGGACCAAUAAGGCUCAUAGAACACCCUUGGAGAAUGAAUGCCUCUGCUGCUGGAGGUCACAGCACCCAGAAAGUGACUAGAGGGAGCAGCUGAUACCUGCUCUAGUGAGUUGUGCUAUUCCUGUCACAUCCUUGCAGAGGUCCAAGGGUUGCUGGCAAGUGAAGGAAUAUCAUGCCUGUAGUUUGAAGGAUAGAUCACUCAACUCUCAACUAUUCUCUCUUCAGCUGUGAACCAUACAACGUUUUUGAAAAGCAAAGUCUGAACAUUUGCAUUCUAUACAGAAUAUUACAGUUGGAAAAUAGGUGUGGUGUCUAGAGAAAUGCUUCUAAAUGCUGCAAGCCACCCUAUGUGAAGCCUAGUCUAGAAAUCUGCUUUGCUUCAUUUAUUAACUUCAUUGUAUCUUUGGAAGUAGAAGUUCUUAAAAGUGUGUACAGAAGAUGAGUCCUCAGCAUGAGUUUCACUGCCUGUCUGUGUGAGAGGAAGUGACCUUGAGAGCAGCUGUAGCCCUAGGGGGACACCCAGGUAGAGGUGCUCACAACAUGCUCUGACACCCGGUAUGGCUGCAUUCCCAGCUUAAAUGAUCACAUCUGCUCUUGGUUUUUUCACUGUUUACAAAAUCUGAUUUCUUUAAAGGGAAGGGAUGGAAAAGGUAGUCAAUGCUCCUCUGAGCACCCAAAGCAUCCCUCCACAAGAACAAAGAGGAAAAAUCAUUACUUGCUCCCAACAUUACACAAAGCGCAUCUCUACCAAUGGAACUCUGCAGUGUCGGUCUAGCCAUCAGCCUUUCCCACCUCACAGCAUAUUUUCUGUGGGGGUAAUUUAUUAGAGGGGAAUUUGUUCCUUUUUACUCUUUUUACUCUUCAAAUUAGUAAUAGAACCCCUCAUGUCAUUCUAAGUGACUUAAGUUUUAAAGGGAACCAGAAAAGGAGAGAAUAUGCUAUUGUGGCACUUCUAAAAUGCAGAGUGUCCUCAAAGAUGGUUAUAGUGGGUAAUGGGUUUCAUAUAAAUUGCAUACUAGAGUAUCUCCAUUUCCUCUUUUAAUUUUUUAAUUGGUUUUUUAAAGCUUGAUAUGCUGAGUUAGUUUUCAUUUAAAAACAAUGCUUGAGUAGGAAAGUUAAAGAAAUAGAAAUUGCCUGUUUUAAUCUAUUCAUCCUGGCAGCAGGUAUGUAUUGUAUCUGUCCAGAGUCCAAAACGUCAGCUCCCUCCACUUGCCUUCCCCAUUUCACAUAAACUAUAAAAGUUAGAAAUAAUAUAUUAUGUCAUAUCCUAACAUCAGUUCAAUGAAUAUAGUUUUUAAAAUACCUACUAUGUGCUAGAUACUGAGGACAGAAUGAUAAAAUACAAAACAAAGCUAACUAAAAACACAGUUUAACUAGUCUUGUCUACGAUUACCUGCCCUAACUAUAACUUCAUUUAAGGGGAGAUACUGCUAAAGGGAGUUCCUUCUGUGACUGCACACUCUGAUACCAAUAUGUGACUUCUCCCUGGCUACAACUGAUUAAAUGAGGGAAGAAAACUGAUCCAAGGGGAGUUAGUCCAAUAGCUUGUAAAUGGUGGGUUCUUAUCAGAGUUUUCUCACUAAGUUAGAACCAAGAGGCUGAGGGUUGUGGGGGCUACUUAAGCAGAAAGUUUCAUGGAGUAUGGACUGUGCACCAUUGUGAAGUUUCCUGUAUUUCCACAGGCUGUGGGGGCAGAGAGCAUCAGAGUGCUGAUCAGGAAAAAAGAAUGAGGCAGAUGCAGACAGAGAAGCAAAGAAGCAUGAGAGGAUGAGAAUUAGGAAGUAGACUCUUUUUUCAUUUUAAUUAAUUUGACUAGAUUAUAUUUCUUGCAAUCAAAAGGGCCCUGUGCAGAGAAGGUCCUUAUCUUCGUUCAUUUUUUGUUGCUAUAGCUGAAUACCCGAGACUGGGUAAUUUAUAAAGUAAAGAAAUUUAUUGCUUACCAUUUUAGAUGCUGGGAAGUACAAGGUCAAGGGUUCUCAUCUAGUGAGGGCCUUCUUGCUAGUGGGGUCUCUGUAGAGUCCUGAGGUAACACAGAGCAUCACAUGGUGUGGGGGUGGGAUUCACCAGAGAGAGCCAAACUGACUUUUAUAACAGACUCACUUUUGUGGUAACUAACCCACUCCCUUGAUAGCCCAUCAAUCCAUUAAUCUAGAAAUAAAUUCAUUCACUCAUGAGGGCAGAGCUCUUGUGAACCAAUCACCUCCCAGAAGUCCCACCUCUCAACACUGCUGCACUGGGGACCAAAUUUCCAACACAUGAACUUUUCGGGGACACAUUCAAGCCACAACAGUCCUCAAUAAAUAUUUGUUGAAUCAAUAAAUACACAGGACAUAGUGUCCUAAAUGCUUGGCAUGUACAUGAACCAGAUUUGGUCCUUGAUGUCACAGAGCUUAUAAUAUAGUGGAGGAGACAGACUUUACAUGUUUGAUCUUGACUGUAAAACUAGGGUCACUACUCAUCAUCUGAUGAAGGAGGCAGACAGUAAAACAAAUAACAACUAUUCAACAUGGUAACGUCAAAACUGAACAGAGGCUCAAGUGAAAGUUUCAAUGAUAGUAACCAUGGCCAAUGGAUAGGUGAAUGCAUUGGAAAAUUAGUAUGAUGCCAUUAGCAAAAACAUAAAUUGCACUUAACUAAAGUUCAUCUGGCUGAAUUCUUUCCUUCCUUCCUUCCUUCCUUCCUUCCUUCCUUCCUUUCUUCCUCUAUCUUUCUUUGGUUUUGAGAUCUGUCUAUAGUAUUGUGCUAGUGCACAUAUUUUAAUUUGGUGCAAGGCAUGCUUAACAGAGUAAGUGAAAAGCUAUAAAGGUUAGAGCGUGUAUUAGUUUCAAUGACGAAGGAGUAAUAAAUCAUUUUGUCAGGUUGCACUCUAACAUUCAAAUUCCAUUUUUAUUAUGGCUAACUAGCCAAGCAUUUAUAAUUCUGAACUCCACAGAAUGGGGAAAAAGUGUAUUAACUUAUAAUAGAUCAUUGAGCUUGUUAAAUGUACCUUUCCUAAUUCGUACUUUUUCCCUUUUGCUGAGAAAAAUGCCUUUCUGAAUAUAUAAUUUUUACAGGUCAUUGGAAAGGAGUACUGCACAACAGGAUUAUUAUAAUGUGCUAAAAGAUGGCACUUGUAUCUCAUUGCCACAUAGAGAGCUCAUGUGAAAACUCUUUGAUCUUUGCUGGCUUUUUAGCUGAAAAGAUUUGGAAAUCUUUUUGGCACUGGCAAAAACAGAACUGUGGUAACUGUUUAUAGUUGGUUGAUUUUUAGCAAUGGGUAAGAAUGUCUUUGUUGAAUCCAGUUUAUUAAUACGUAAUGGGCAACAUGUUGCCUUAAAGGCAAAAGCAUAUUUUUCUCAUAUCAAAAAGCUCCCUAAAUUUUUGCCAAUAUCCAAAGAUAUUUUAAGAUGGUCUUCAUUUUCUUUUUCAGUCUGUCCUAUGCUGAGAAAAAAAAAUUACAACCUCUGAACUUCAGCAGUUUUUUAGGUAAAAGGAAUUUUUCAUGAUGUGAUUGAUAUAACUACUCAGCUGGACAUAAGCUUUCAAGGGCUAAGUCCAUUUGCCGAUUUGUUUGCAUUUCCUACUCCAACUAAAAUAAUUCAAAGACAUGAAGUGUCUAUUGUGGAAAAUGCAUGAAUAAUGCAAAAGUCAUUCUCAAGUGACCUAUCAGAAAGGCCUACCAGAAAUGCAGUUACUGCUUUCUAAUAAAAUCAUGAAAAACUUUUUUAAAAAGUAUAACCAUCUUGAAUUUGUUGAGGCAAUUAUAAGAGAGUAUAUAAGGGCAAGUUUCUCCAAAAGCGGUUCUGUUUGUUUUGUUUUUUUUUAAUAAUUCCCAUCAACAGCAAUCUGUUUUCUCAUUGUAGUAGUAUAGGUGUUAACAUAAAAGCUCAAACAGCUUGGGAGAAAAAAAAGGAUAUAGCAAACCUAACUGAUAACUUUGCUAGUUUCAAAUCAUUAUGAUGGCCAUUCAUAGAUGACUGAAAUAUUUAACAUUUGAAGUAACAGAAUUUUGACUUAUGUUUUCAUGGUUUAAGAGUUUAUAUUUCAAAUUUUUUCACAUAGUCUGUUUAUAACAGUAUAUAAAACAUGUAUUAACUAUAUAAGUUAAUAAAGUCAUGAACUGAUGGCCAUUUUUUGGUCUUAUUCAUAUAGUAUAGGCUGUUUUGUGAAUUAAUCCCCUUCCCAUGUGUUUGAAUUCCCCACUAUGUAAGGCUUAGUGGUGUUAGCAUGAUCCAAGGGUGGGAUUUUCAGCCCUCUGACAUCAAAAGGUGAAGCAGAGGACACAAAAACCCUCACUGCAUCUUCCCUAGACUGGCCAGAACCACUCCAUGGUCAGUGGACUCCCUUAAUAGGAAGGAAUGCUGGUCAGUUGUCAAAGAGCAAAAAGGGAGGGGUAGUCAUGAGGUUGGUUGUAAUCAGAGGUGCAACAGGUCUUUCCAAAGGGCUGGUUUCUGUUUAACUCUUAGGAAAGAACACCUAAUGGUAGUUAGUGAGGAGGGGGUAUAAUGAGAUGUGCCCAACCUCCCAUCCCAUCAUGGCCGGGAACUCAGUUUUUAAGGUUUCCCUGAAGUCCUCUUGGCCAGGAGAGGGUCUGUUUAGUCAAAUGUGGGGGGGGAGCUUAGGAUUUUAUUUUUAUUUCCAAGUUAUAAUGUUGGACCAUCAGAGCAUGAAUACAGGUUGAGUCUUUAAUCUGUAAAUACUUAGCAAUCACCUUCUUCUCAGUAACUUUCUCUGAAGGUUGCUGAUAAGCCAGUGUUCUUGAUGUUUGCCCACUUACCCCUCAAGAUGAGGAGUGAAGAAAUUAGAUUGCAUUGCCAGGAAUUUCCUAGAAGAAAAGGUUUUGAGGAUGCAUGACCUAUGAGGGUGCUGAGGACCCCUUUCCACCAAACAUGGACUAACUUCUGGGUUGCUCUUUCACAUCUAUUGUCUUGUUCGACGUACACAGAAGUGCAGAGCACAGCCGCAGCCCUCACAGCAUCAUCUAUCUAGGUUCUGAAUCCUGAAUGGUCUGAGGCUCUCCUAGAGCUGAGAUUCUCCUUUGCAGUUCCAGUGGAGAAAAGCACUUUCUUUGCCGAGGCAGUGUAACUUCCUUGUUCCCAAGGCUCCAACUGUUGUGGGCACAUAUGAGUAUACAUUAACAUCCAUGCCCAAUUUAUAAUCACUGUUUUCCCCACAUGUGUACUCAGACCUCCAAGCUUCUGAAAAAUAUUUCCUCUCAUCUCUCAAAGAAUUUUAGUACAUUUGCCUGGAUGCAGAAACACAAAUCAUGCUGGCUUUCCUACUCAAUCAAAAACUGUAGCUUGAGUGGGGUGGCAAGGGUUGUCCCACAGCAGGUUUACUUGGACUCCAAAAUGAUGUAGAGUUUAGUGAGGCAGCUCCUUGAGUUUGAACUUAGAGCCCUUUUGGCUACCAGGGCACCUGCAGUCCUCCAAGAUAGUAGAGUCUGAACCAGUUAAAGAGCCAGCUACCACAGCUUUGCAGAAACCACUGUUUCUCCUUAACUCUAGGGCUCAGCGGUUGAACUCCUUAGAAUAAAACUUUCUGUCUGCGACCCUAUCAUUUUCUUUUGUAUUUUGGCCUUCACUGAAUUCCCACCCCAUCCAUUCCAACAGACUUGGUUAUACGUGUCUGAACACCAAAUGUGACAGAAUUUGUGGCCUUGGAUCAGGAGGCUAUUUGGCCCUUAUCUAAAUCGGUGGCUGAGAAUGGAUUCCAGGGAAGUGUUUUUCUUAGGAGUACCCAAGAAGCUCAGCUCAGGUUGGGCUCCCUGUUCUAUUCUGAGAACUACAAAUCAAAUUCAAAAUGGAGCACAGAAAAUUCUCAUUUCUAGUUGACUUAUUUGUAUUUUGGUGUCCUGUGCCCUAAAUAUCUUCUCAAGGAAACCUUGGCUUUAAAAGUGAUUGUUUACUUAAACAAAUAAAACAACAACAUACAAGAAAAGGCAGUAAAUCCGAGCGUCCAUCAACAAAUGAAUCAAAAAACAAAUGAGAUAUAUAUGUACGGUGGCAUAUUAUUCAGCCUUAAAAAGGAAAGAAAUUUUGACACAUGAGACAAUAUGAAUGAACCUUGAAGACAUUAAUUAUGCUGAGUGAAAUAAGCCAGCCACAAAAGAACAGAUAUUGUAUAAUUCCUCUUAUAUUAGGUACCUAAAAUAGUCAAAUUGAUAGAAAGUAGAAUGUUGGUUGGCAGGGGCUGGCAAGGAGAGGGAAAUGAAGAGAAGGUGUAUGAAGGGAACAGAGUUUCAGUUGGGGAAGACGAAAAAGUUCUGACAGUGGAUGAUGGUGGUUGUUGCACAGCAACAUGAAUGUACUUAAUGCCACAGAACUGUAUGCUUAAAAAUGGUUGAAACGGUAAAUUUGAUAUAAUGUGUAUUGAACCUAUUUCCAGAUCAAAACAGAGAGAUCUACAUUCCUUUUGGUGGUGUCAAAAUAAACCAUUAUCUUGAAAUAGC